CAAAUAGUCUGUGGCAACCCUGCAUUAAGGAAGUCUAUCAGCAUCAUUUUUCCUGUUGCACAUGUUUACUUUCUGUUUCUGUGUCAUAUUUUGGCAGUUCUUGCAAUAUUUCAAAACUUUUCAUUAUUAUUAUAUCUGUUAUGGUGAUCUUUGAUCAGUAAUUUUUUGAUGUUACUAUUGUAAUUGUUUUGAGGCACCACAAACCACACCCAUAAGGGACAGCAAACUUAGUCAAUAAAUGUGUGUUCUGACUACUCCACUGACCCACCAUUCCCCCAUCUUUCCCCCUCUGUUCAGGCCUCCCUAUUACGUGAUACACAACCACUUGAAUUUAGGCCAAUUAAUAAACCUACAAUGGCCUGGUGUUUAAGUGAAAGGAGGAGUCAUAUGCUUCUUACUUGAAAUCAAAAGCUAGAAAUGACUAAGCUUAGUGAGGAAGGCAUAUCAAAAGCAAACAUAAGCCAAAAGUUAGACUUCUUGCUCUAAACAGCCAAAUUGUGAAUGCAAAGGAAAAGUUAUUGAAGGAAAUUGAAAGUGCUACUCUAAUGAACACAUGAAUGAUAAGAAAGUGGCAGCCUUAGUGCUGAGAGAAAGUUUUAGUGGUCUGAAUGGAAGGUCAUACCAACCACAACAUUCCUUUAAGCCAAAGCCGUCAGAAGAAGACCCUAACUCUCUUCAUUUCUCUGAACACUGUGAGAGAGGUGAGGAAACUGCAGAAGAAAAGUUUGAAGCUAGCAGAGGUUGGUUUGUGAGGUUGAAGGAAAGAAGUGUCUCCGUAAUGUAAAAGUGCAAGCUGAAGCAGCAAGUGCUAAUGUAGAAACUAUAGCAAGCUAUCUAGAAAAUCUAGCUAAGAUAAUUGGUAAAGAUGGCUGCACUAAACCACAGAUUUUCAAUAUAGAUGAAAAAGCCUUCUAUUGGAAGGAGAUGCUAUCUAUGACUUCCAUAGCUAGAGAGGAGAAGACAAUACCUGGCUUCAAAAGACAAGUUAUAACUCUCUCAUUAGGGGCUAAUGCAGCUGGUAACUUUAAGUUGAGGCCACUGCUCAGGUACCAUUCCCAAAAUCCUAGGGCCCUUAAGAAUUAUGCUAAGUAUACUCUGCCUGUGCUCCAUAGAUGGCACAGUGAAAGCUUGGAGACAGCAUUUACAGAAUGCUUUACUGAAUAUUUUAAGCCCACUGUUGAGACCUACUGCUCAGAAAAAGAUUUUUUACAAAGCAUUACUGCUCAUUGAGAAGGCACUUGGUCACCCAAGAGCUCUGAUGGAGAUGUACAAGGACAUUAGUAUUGUUUUCAUGCCUGUUAAUACAACAUCCAUUCUGCAGCCCAUGGACCAAGGAGUAAUUUCAAUUUUCAAGUGUUAUUAUUUAAGAAAUACAUUUUGAGCCAGGUGCAGCAGCUCACACCUGUAAUCCUAGCACUUCGGGAGGCCAAGGCAGGCAGAUUGCUUAAGCCUAGGGGUCCAAGACCAACCUGAGCAGCAUACAAAACCCUAUCUAUACUGAAAAUGCAAAAAAUUAGUGAAGCGUGGUGUCAUGCACUUGUAGUCCCACCUACCCAGGAUGCAGAGGUGGGAGGAUCACGUGAGCCAGAGAGUCGAGGCUGCAGUGAGCCACAAUCGCACCACUGCACUCCAGCCUGGGUGACAAAGUGAGACCCCCAUCUCAAAAAAAAAAAAAAAAAAAAGGAUAUUUUGUAAGGCUAUAGCUACUGUAGCUGCUAUUGAUAGUGAUUCCUCUGACACUCUGAUGGAUAUCUGGGCAAAGUAAAUUGAAAAUGUUUUGGUGGCAGUGUGGUAGCUCACACCUGUAACUCCCAGCACUUUGGGAGGCCAAGGUGGGUGAAUCGCUUGAGGUCAGGAGUUUGAAACCAGCCUAGCCAACAUGGUAAAACCCUGUCUCUACUAAAAAUAUAUAUAAAAAUUAGUGUGGUGGCAUGGUGUCACAUGCCUGUAAUCCCAGCUACUUAGGAGGCUGAGGCAGGAGAAUUGCUUGAAGGCAGGAGGCAGAGGUUGCAGUGAGCUGGGAUCGCACCACUGCACUCCAGCCUGGGCAACAGAGCAAGACUCUGUCUUUAAAAAAAAAGAAAAAAAGAAACACAAAAAAAAUGUUUUGGAAAGGAUUCACUAUUCUAGAUGCCGUUAAGAACAUUCGUGAUUGGUGGGAGGAAAUCAAAAUAUCAGCCUUAACAGAAGUUGAUUCCAACCCUCAUGGAUGACUUUGAGGGGCUCAAGACUUAAGUGGAGGAAUUAAUUGGAGAUGUAGUGGAAAUAAAUAGCAAGAGAAAUAGAAUUAGAAGUGGAGCCUGAAGAUGGGACUGAAUUAUUGCAAAGGCAUGGUAAAACUUGAGUGGAUGAGAAGUUGCUUCUUAGGGAUGAGCAAAGAAAAUGGUUUCUUGAAAUGGACUCUACUCCUGGUGAAGAUGGUGUGAACAUUAUUGACAACAAAGGAUUUAGAGUAAGCUUUUCUAACCUGUGGCCCCCAGGACGGCUUUUCUAACCUGUGGCCCAGGAUGGCUCUGAAUGUGACCCAACACAAAUUCAUAACCUUUCCUAAAACAUGAGAUUUUUUUUCUUUUUUUGAGACAGAGUUUCUCUUGUCUCCCAGGCUGGAGUGCAAUGGCACGAUCUUGGCUCACUGCAACCUCCGUCUCCUGGGUUCAAGCAGUUCUCCUGCCUCAGCCUCCCAAGCGAUUACAGUCGCCCACCACCACACCCAGCUAAUUUUUGUAUUUUUAGUAGAGACAGGGUUUCACCAUGUUGGCCAGGCUGGUCUCGAACUCCUGACCUCAGGUGCUCGCCCGCCUGGGCCUCCCAAAAUGCUGGGAUUACAGGCAUGAGCCACCAUGCUCGGCCGAGAUUUUUUUUUUUUUUUUUUUUUUUAAAGCUCAUCUGCUAUGGUUAGUGUUAGUGUGUUUUAUGUGCAGUCCAAUUCUUCCACUGUGGCUCAGAGAAGCCAAAAAAUUGGACACCCCUGAUUUAGAAUAUAAACUUUAUUGAUAAAGCAUCAGCAGGAUUUAAAAAGAUUGACUCAAAUGUUGUGAAAGAAGUUCUGUGGGCAAAAUGUUAUCAAACAGCAUUGCAUGCUACAGAGAAAUCUUUUGUGAAAGAAUCAAUUGAUGUGGCAAACUUCACUGUUGUCCUAUUUUAAGAAAUUGGCAGGCCAGGCACGGUGGCUCAUGCUUAUAGUUCCAGCACUUUGGCAGGCUGAGGCAGGCGGAUUGCUUGAGCCCAGGAGCUCAAGACCAUCCUGGGCAACAUGGUGAGACCCUGUCUACAAAAAAUACAAAAAUUAGCUGAACAUGGUGAUGCAUGCCUGUAGUCCAGCUCCUUGGGAGGCUGAGGCAGGAGAAUUGCUUGAGCCCAGGAGGUCAAGGCUGCAGUGAGCCGUGAUCACAUCACUGCAUUUCAUCCUGGGCAGCAGAGCGAGACCCUAUCUUGGGAAACAAAAAAGAAAGAAAGAAAUUGCUACAGCCACCCUACCGUUCAGCAGUCACCACCCUGAUCAGUCAGCAGCCAUCCACUCAAGCACCGAACAAGAUUUGUGAUGAAAUGGAGCCUGGAACAAACUCUUUUCGGGUAGAAUUUCCUGAUUUUUCCAGCACCAUUCUACAGAAACUGAACCAGCAGCGCCAGCAAGGACAAUUAUGUGACGUCUCCAUUGUUGUCCAAGGCCACAUUUUCCGGGCACACAAAGCCGUUCUUGCUGCCAGUUCACCCUACUUUUGUGACCAGGUACUCCUGAAAAACAGCAGGAGAAUUGUUUUGCCUGAUGUGAUGAACCCAAGAGUGUUUGAGAACAUUCUCCUAUCUAGUUAUACAGGACGUCUAGUAAUGCCCGCUCCAGAAAUUGUUAGUUACUUGACAGCGGCAAGCUUCCUCCAGAUGUGGCAUGUGGUAGACAAAUGCACUGAAGUUUUAGAGGGAAACCCUACAGUCCUUUGUCAGAAGCUAAAUCAUGGCAGUGACCACCAGUCACCAAGCAGCAGUAGUUAUAAUGGCCUGGUAGAGAGCUUUGAGCUGGGCUCUGGGGGUCAUACUGAUUUUCCCAAAGCCCAAGAACUGAGAGAUGGUGAAAAUGAAGAGGAGAGCACCAAAGACGAGCUGUCAUCCCAGCUCACCGAGCACGAAUACCUGCCCAGCAACUCGUCCACAGAGCAUGACCGCCUGAGCACGGAAAUGGCAAGCCAGGAUGGGGAGGAGGGCGCCAGCGACAGCGCCGAGUUCCACUACACCCGGCCCAUGUACAGCAAGCCCAGCAUCAUGGCUCACAAACGCUGGAUCCACGUGAAGCCCGAGCGCUUAGAACAGGCUUGCGAGGGCAUGGAUGUGCACGCGACCUACGACGAGCACCAGGUCACAGAGUCCAUCAACACCGUGCAGACAGAGCACACGGUGCAGCCUUCGGGAGUGGAGGAGGACUUCCACAUCGGGGAGAAGAAAGUGGAAGCUGAGUUUGAUGAACAGGCUGAUGAAAGCAAUUAUGAUGAGCAGGUGGAUUUCUAUGGCUCUUCCAUGGAAGAGUUUUCCGGAGAGAGGUCAGAUGGGAAUCUAAUUGGGCACAGACAGGAGGCUGCCCUCGCAGCAGGUUACAGUGAGAAUAUUGAAAUGGUAACAGGGAUUAAAGAAGAAGCUUCCCACUUAGGAUUCUCAGCCACUGACAAGCUGUAUCCUUGUCAGUGUGGGAAAAGUUUCACUCACAAGAGUCAGAGAGAUCGGCACAUGAGCAUGCACCUCGGUCUUCGGCCUUACGGCUGUGGGGUCUGCGGUAAGAAAUUCAAAAUGAAGCACCAUCUCGUGGGCCACAUGAAAAUUCACACAGGCAUAAAGCCGUAUGAGUGUAAUAUCUGUGCAAAGAGGUUUAUGUGGAGGGACAGUUUCCACCGGCAUGUGACUUCUUGUACUAAGUCCUACGAAGCUGCAAAGGCUGAGCAGAAUACAACUGAGGCUAACUAAAAAUAGGAUCUGGCCCUUGAGUGGCAUGCACAAAAAUAAACUAUGGUAAUUAAUGCAAAUCUGGGCACAGAUGAUGCGUGCUACUUGCUAUUAUGAGAGAAGCUUAAAAAAAAAAAGGAAGAUAUUUCUGAAAGACCAGCUCUAAGUAGGCCAAUUAAAAAAAUCUAAUUCCUCAAAUUUGUGUGUUCCAGUCCUGGCCUGGAAUGGGUAAUGGGGUGAGUUAACCCACCGCCCAGCUGGCAAGGGAAACCUUCUGACUGGUUGUGAUCGAAACAGGUGGACAGAGACACCUGCACUUGGAACUGGACUCCACCCACCAGUUCCAUUUUGGGUGGCAGCAGCUUUGGAUCACUCAUUAUUACAAGGUCAUGCUGAAAUUUUAUUUUGCUCUUGCUAUAGAUACUUAGGUAAUGUGGAUUUGUUUUGGUAGCUAUUUCACUGAAGGAAGUGCUACUUAUAUAAAAGCUAGAAAUAAUGUGAUUCCUAGGAUGAGAAAUUGGUUAACAGAGCUCUGUUGUCUGGUUUUAGUCUUUCUAAAGGAUAUUUUAACUAAAACUAUGGAGAUGCUAAGAGAGUGACUUUCUAAAUAUGAAACAGAUAAUUUACGGUACAAGGCUGACAUAGUGCCCUUGUCAGUUUCUGUAAGAUGCCACUACUGUCACAAGGUGUUUCAGACUCUUGAUAAGGCAGUGUUUUGUAUUUUAGUUCUAACAUUGAGUUUGGACAAUUUUAUCUAAUUGUAAUUCUCUAGGGUGCCAGAGAUAGGUAUUUCUCAUUGGUUUGCUUUCCCAAAUCCUGUUUGGUUAAUUGUAGCCUCCAUACAGUGGGGUCUUCUCUGUGGCUGGUAGACACCAAGCUGCUGUGACUGACCACGGUACCACGGGCUGCCACAGCCCCUGCUCUGUCUUAGAUUAUGGUGCUUUACAAAGAGAGUGGUCCAUGACCACACUUAGUGAGAAGGAGCCACAAGUUGUGGCUGAGAGUUCCCUGUGAACUUGAGUAGUUCAUAGAGUGCUAAGGUGACACUCCACCAACCAGAGUGAGAGGGCAGAUAGGCAGGAUUCUAUGAGUGGUUAUACUUAAGGGGGACAAAACUGCCCAAGAAGAAUCUUGAGAAUACACUCUUUCAAGGUGGGGGAGAUACUCUUUAGAGGGUACACUGAGCUAAUACUACCAGUUCUUUAUGAGCACUGGAAUGUGUUUGUAAAAGGAGUCCUAAGUUUAGCAAGGUAGUCUACAGAACCAUGCUCCCACAUUAUAGAUAAAGCUGCUUAAACUUAAAAGUCCACAAAGCUACGCCGACCAGAAAAAAAAAAUUAAAAAAACAAACAAGAAAAGCAACUAUUCUGAGACCUUUUCUGCCCAUCAGUUAGAUGAUUUAGGUUAAAAAGAAAGGUAAUAUUGCACAUGCUUUUAAGCUGUGUAACAUACCUGAGGUUAUCACCAGGGUAGGACAGGGUGCUACUACCAUGUCAUCUUUUCCACAAUCGUACUGGGUUAUUUACUUCUAAAUAGAAACUUUUUUUUCUUAAAAUAAAAAUAAUUUUUCUUGGAUUUGGGGUGAAAUUUUAUUUGAAAAGUUUGGCUUUGCUGUAAUGUAAUAGACAUUGCUGGCAAUGGCCUCUGAUUCUCAAGCUCCUAACACCAGGGUGUUUACUUGUUGAACAUUGUCUGGAAAGAGGAAAGAAAAUACUUAUUUACCAGUUAACUCUUGUAAGCAAGAUUACAAACAGGGAUUUAUUCACAACACUGUAUCAUUCUCGAUAUAUAAAAAGCACUUUGUAUUUAAAACUUUAUUAUAAAUAUAUAUAUAUAUUGUUUUUUUUUAAACCUAGAAACUAGAUAUUACCUCUUGGUUGUUUGCCACAUUAAUAGCUUCUCUUAGUAUUGAAACGUUACUGGUUAGCAGUCUUUUCUCUGUGUACCUGACACACGUAUACUGAGGGGAUUGUACAAUCAAGCCUAUUGUCUCCUUUUCUUUCACUCAUGGUAGAGGCCAGUGGGUUUUAGGUAUGAUCCUAGCCAUUAUAUUUGAGGAGAAAUUGUUCUAUUACUCCUACUAAUUUCAGUACUAAGGUGGUGAUGCCAUUUUGUUCUGCCAAAAACUGAUCACCCUCUCCCAUGGUAUUAGCAGAGCAUUUUCUGCCUGUUUGGAAGGUUUGAUGUCCUGUUUCUCAUUGAAGACUAUUUACAUGAUCAUUAGGACAUUGCAGGAGAAGUCUGAGAGGUAAAAAUACAGAUAUUCUGGGAGAGUCGUGGUCCUUCAGUUCUGCUGAAAUCAGCAUAGUGCCCUUGUCAUGAGGAAGAGUUUCUGUUCAGCCAAGAGUGGUGGCACGCUUGGGUGGUAGUUUUGGAAGCAGUCAGUUGUGCUAGGACUUAUUUAAUAUGUUGUGAAGAGAAGAGUGUCUUCUUGAAAGCCUUAUGUGUCCAUCAGCUACUAAAUGUAGAACUUAAAUAAGUUGCUCACAUCUGUUCUUUUAGUGUUUUGUGGUAUUUGAGGUUUUGGCAAAAAUUGGGAUUUUUUUAUCAGGCAGCCAGAGCCUGGGAGGUGGUAGGGUGUCUGAAAUGCUGGCCAUGUUCAGAGAGGCAGGAGAAGGGGGUUGCUUUCAUUUGAAUAUUAAAAGUGAAUUUUUGUAAACUCUGGUUUUUACCUUUUUUUCAUCCCCACGUUGAGUUGGAGGAAUAGUCUCUUCUCUUCACCUCAAUAUAGCUUUAGAAAAUCUUUAUCCUUCCUAAUAAGUUUGGAUGGUUGUGGGUAACAUUGUUCAAACAAUCUUUCAGGGAUCACGUCAAUGGCCUACAACCAAGCUAUUUGUCCCCUACUUUGAGUCUUAACUGUGGUUUUUCUUCAAUCCCCAUGGGAAAGGGCUUCAAGGCACCACCAGUGGUAUUUAAUAUUCAUACUUGGGGCCAGGCAUGGUGGCUCACGCCUGUAAUCCCAGCACUUUGGGAGGCCGAGAUGGGUGGAUCACCUGAGGUCAGGAGUUUGUGACCAGCCUGACCAACAUAGUGAAACCCCAUCUCUACUAAAAAUACAAAAAUUAGCCAGGCGUGGUGGCGCACACCUGUAAUCCCAGCUACUCGGGAGGCGGAGGCAGGAGAAUCACUUGAACCUGGGAGGCGGAGGUUGCAGUGAGCCGCGAUUGCACCACCACACUCCAGCCUGCGCGACAGAUCGAGACUCUGUCUCAAAAAAAAAAAAAAAAUUCAUACUUAUGCCAUGCUUUUACCUUUAGAUACACACGUUACAGUAAUCCACGUGGUGAAGUGCAUGUCACCGUUAACUAAGGAAGGACUGCGGUAACUUACCCUGCAGGGCUGUAGGUUGCCUGCAGGCGCUCCAGGCCCCCAGCCUGUUGAUUCCGAUUUCUAGGUCUCAUCUUCCUCUGGUCCCUUUUGGCCACUACUUUAAAAGCUUGCCCAAAGGGAUCCCCUCCAUUCUAGUGGGCAUUUGCUGAACUAACCUGCCCCUAAGGCUGGCUUCUAACCACCGGGGAAAGCUGCUUAGCCUCCAGGGCUCCCUCCUUGAGAGGCUCACACACCCCCAAGCUGCUGUGGAGUGAAUUUGAGACGGAGCAGAAGCUGCAAAGCUGUGCUUUCCCUGGGGAAGGGGAUGUGCUGCGGCCUCCUGGGUGGGCGUGGAGAGGGCGCCAUCACAACGAGUCCAGGUUUUUGCUUUUGGAAGGUCUCUGAUAAUUUAGGGGUGCUGGAAACCAGCACUGUGUUAUCCCCAAUCCCUCCUGUGCCACCAGUUUUGUGAUUUAGGUUGCUUUAGUGGGUGACUAACUUUUGUUCAGUGAAACCAGGGUUUGUUUGGGGUUUUUUUCUUUGCUACUUACAUAUUUAAAGGUACAAGUUUCUUAUUUCAAAUCUCUACUGAUAGUGCCCUAUGGGGAGAUGCUGGAACACAUUUUGCAAAUGUGACUUUUUUUUUUUUUUUUAAUUUUUGCUUGAAGCCUGUGUCAUGUUAGUUGCUGCUGCCUUCUUUCCUUUUGUGAGGUUCCCAAUGUUUCGUCCAGAAAAGUACUUUAUUUAUGCAAGUCAGGUGACUCUUAGGCCACAAAACCAUUUGAUGAUAAACAGAUUAUCAUUAGGUGCAUAUCUUAUUGAUAUUUUGUGAAAUGUUAUGCCUAUGUUGCAAAAGUUGAAUAGUUUUGUCUUUAUAUAUUGCUGUCUUCAGUGUACAGCAUGGUUUUACUUAAUUGAAUGUUAAUGUUUAAUAUUUUCUUCUUAUAGAAGAGAUCAUGCCCUUUUGUAUGACAUGUUUUAAUAAAUGUUAUCUGUCAACUUUGUAAAA